UUUUUUUUUUUUUUUUUUUUGGGAGACAGAGUCUCCCUCUUGUCACCCAGGCUGGAGUGCAGUGGCGCAAUCUUGGCUCACUGCAACCUUCACCUCCCAGGUUCAAGCAAUUCUCCUGCCUCAGCCUCCCAAGUAGCUGGGACUACAGGCGUAUGCCACCGCAUCUGGCUAAUUUUUGUAUUUUUAGUGGAGACAGGGUUUCACCAUGUUGGCCAGGAUGAUCUCGAUCUCUUGACCUCAUGAUCUGCCUGCCUUAGCCUCCCAAAGUGCUGGGAUUACAGGCAUGAAUCACCGCGCCCGGCCAGUCCCCAACCUUUUUGGCACCAGGGACUGGUUUUGUGGAAGACAAUUUUUCCAUGGUGGGGGAAUGUUUUGGGGAUAAAACUCUUUCACCUCAGAUCACCAGGCAUUAGAUUCUCAUAAGGUGUGCAACCUAGAUCCCUCACAUGCACAGUUCACAGUAGGGUUCACGGUCCCAUGACAAUGAGAAUCUAAUGCUCCUAUUGAUCUGACAGACAGAGCUCAGGUGGUAAUGCUCCCCGGUAGGCUGCUCACCUGCUCUGUGGCCUGGUUCCUAAUGGGGUUUGAGGAGAUUUAUUGGUUGGCAGCCAGGUGUUGGGGACUCCUCCAAUAAUGUACUUAGAAGUAGAAUUGCUGGAUCAUAAUGUGUGUGUGUAUUUGACUUUACUAAGUAAUGUUAAACUUUAAUCCAAAUUGUUAUUUUAUAUUCCCACCAGUAAUGGGUGAAAAUUCACAUUUCUUUAUGUCUUUACCAAUACUUGAUAUUCUUAGAUUUUAGAAUUUUUGUCAAAAUAGUAGGUGUAAAAUAAUGUCUUAUGGUUUUUAUUUGUAUUUACUUGAAUACAAAUAAAUACAAGGCUGAGGCUUGAGAUUGAGAUUGAGAUUGAGGCUGAGCACCUUUCUAAUAUUUAUGGGGCAGUUGUGUUUCCCCUUCCAUGAAAUGUCUGUACAUGACUUUUGCCCAUUUUAGAAAACUGAGGAUUUGUUUUUAUUAAAACUUUGUUAUUAUUUAUCCUGGAUAUUUCCUUUAUAGGUUAUAUGUGUCCCAGUGUGUGACUUAUCUUUCCACUUUUUGUGAUAUGUUGAUUAAGCAGUAGUUCUUAAUGAAAUUGAAUUAGAAUUUUUCUUCAUUUUAUACUUCUUGUGUCUUUCUAAAUAAAUUCUUUCCUAACUCAGGUUAUAAAGAUAUCCUGCUAUGCUUUUACUAAAAGUUUCUGAAUCUUUUGCUUAUCACCGUUAUGUACUUGAUCCAUCUUCAGUUGGUUUUUAUAUAUGGUAUGUGAUAGGGAAUAAUUUGCCAAUGUCCUAGCACUAUAUAUUGGAUGAUCCAUCCUUUCCUCAUGAAUCUAUACUACUGGCUCUUGUUUUAUAUUAUUUUCAUACAAGAUCUGUAUACAAGCUCUCCAUUACGGUGGUCUUUCUGUUUCUGCACUAAUAUCUUAGUAUCUUAAUCACUGUAGCGUAAUCAUGUCUUUAUCUGGCAGGAAAAAUAGUUUUUUGCCUGAUUUUUCUUUAGGAGUGCCUUAGUUGUUCUUGGCUCUUCUAAAUUUAGGAUCAGCAUCUCAAUUUUUCAGAAAAUUGUUUCAAUUUUAAUAGGAAUUAUAAUGUUUAGAGUAUAGGACAAUUGACAUCUUGAGAUAUUAUGGUACUUCCUUAAUACUAUUUAAGGUCUUCUAAAUGUCAUUCAUUAAAGUUUAAAAAUUUUUCUUCAUAAAGGAUUUUCUUUCUUUUUUUUUUUUUUGGAGAAGGAGUCUCACUCUGGCACGAUCUCGGCUCACUGCAGCCUCCGCCUCCUGGGAUCAAGCAAUUCUUAGCCUCAGCCUCCCAAGUAGCUAAGAUUACAGAUGCACACCACCACACCCAGUUAAUUUUUGUAUUUUUAGUAGAGACAAGGUUUUACCAUAUUUGUCAGCCUGGUGUCGAACGCCUGACCUCAAGUGAUCCACCUGCCUUGGCCUCCCAAAGUGCUGGGAUUACAGGCGUGAGUCACUGUGCCCAGCCCAUAAAGGUUUUAUACACAUUUUAUAAGAUUAUUUUCCUAAUUAUUCUAUUACUUUAUUUUUGCAACUAUCAUUAAAAAAUUAUAUUUUCUGUUUGUUGCUUAUGUAGGAGUGCAACUAUCUUUUAUAGAUUAUUUCAACAAUUUUACUAAACUCACUUAUUAACUCUUGUAAUUUUUCUAUAGAUUCUUUUGGGUUUUCAAUUAGAAUAAUUAUAUUACCUGCAAAUAAUAACAGUUUUAUUCCUUCCUUUCCAAUCCUUUUUAUCUUAUUGGCUAGGACCUCCAGACAAUGUUGAGUAGACAUUGUGAUAGUAGGUAUCCUUGUCUUGUCCCUGGUUUUAAAGGUAGUUCUUUUAGUAUUGCACUAUUGAUUAUGAUUUUUGUUGUACACUUUUUGUUUAUAUCCUUUAUCAAGUUUAGGAAAUGUUCUUCUAUUUCUAGGCCCUGAGUUUUUGCUUGUAUAUUUGUUAGGAACCAUGAAUUGUUACCUUUUCUGCAUCUAUUGUCAUUUUUCUCCUUUUAUCUGUUAAUGUGAGAAUCACAAAAGAUUUACUUUUGUUGAACCAGUCUUAGUUCCUGAAAUAAGCCCAAGUCGGUCAUGGUGUAGUAUCUUUUCUAAACAUUCCUAAAUUUGGUUUGCUACCCUUAUUUUUUUUUUUUUAAGGUAAGGUCUCAGUCUGUCACCCAGGCUGGAGUGCAGUGGUUGAUCUUGGCUUACUGCAACCUCCACCUCCUGGGCUGAAGCAAUUCUCCCACCUCAGCCUCCCCAGUAACUGGGACCACAGAUGUGUGCUACCAUGCCUGGCUAAUUUUUGUAUUUUGGGUAGUGAUCGGUUUUUGCCUUGUUACCCAGACUGGUCUCAAAACUCUUGAGCUCAAGCCUCAGCCUCCUAAAGUGGUGGGAUUGUAGGCAUGAGCCAUCACACCCGGCCAAGUUUGCUACUUUUGCUUAUGAUUUUUUUUCAUCUAUGUCCAUGAACAGUUAUUCUUUCCUAGAUAGUGUUGGUUUGGUUUAAUGUCAGUUGUACACAGCACACAUUGUAUAAGGUUGGAAUUGUCUAUUUCUGGAAAGGUAAAAUUACAUUCUUUGUGGGAAGAUUUUAAACCUUUGAUACAAUUUCUUUAAUGAUUAGAAAACCAUUAGAAAUGUUUUAUUUCUUUUUGAGUCAGUUUUGAUAAUUUAUAAUUUUUAGGAAUUUGUUCACUUUACCUAAAUGUUCAAAGCUUGAUUUGAAGUUUUUCAUAAUUUUCUCUUUUUAAACUGUUAUGUUUGUAGUUAUGCCCCUCCUUCUUGUGUAUAAUACAGUAGUAUUUGUGCCUUCUCUUUUUUCUUGAUCUUUUAGCAAUUUUUCUAUUAGUACUUUUCAAAGUGUCAACUUUGUUUUUUAUUUUUUUAAUUUAAAAAAUUUAUUAUAAUAUUUUGAGAUGGAGUCUGUCUGUUUUCUCCAGGCUGGUCUCGGACUCCUAGACUCAGGUAAUCCUCCUGUUUCAGCCUCCCAAGUAGAUGGGAUUAUAGGCGUCAACCACCACACGUGACUUUCAAGUUUGUUUUUUAUUUAUUAACUGUUGCUUUUCUUUAUUUCUUUCCUUCUUUUAGAGGAGAAAAAAAGGCUGAAAAAAUUUAGGAGCCACUUGAUAAAAAAAGAAUUUCAGGUCCAGGGGCAAGUUCAUCCUACUCUCGAGUCUAAUGAUGAUGCUCUUCAGUAUGUUGAAGAAUUAAUUUUGCAAUUAUUAAAUAUGCUAUGCCAAGCUCAGCCCCGAAGUGCUUCAGAUGUAGAGGAACGUGUUCAAAAAAGUUUCCCUCAUCCAAUUGAUAAAUGGGCAAUAGCUGAUGCCCAAUCAGCUAUUGAAAAGAGGAAGCGAAGAAACCCUUUAUCUCUCCCAGUAGAAAAAAUUCAUCCUUUAUUAAAGGAGGUCCUAGGUUAUAAAAUUGACCACCAGGUUUCUGUUUACAUAGUAGCAGUCUUAGAAUACAUUUCUGCAGACAUUUUAAAGCUGGUUGGGAAUUAUGUAAGAAAUAUACGGCAUUAUGAAAUUACAAAACAAGAUAUUAAAGUGGCAAUGUGUGCUGACAAGGUAUUGAUGGAUAUGUUUCAUCAAGAUGUAGAAGAUAUUAAUAUAUUAUCUUUAACUGACGAAGAGCCUUCCACCUCAGGAGAACAAACUUACUAUGAUUUGGUAAAAGCAUUUAUGGCAGAAAUUCGACAAUAUAUAAGGGAACUAAAUCUAAUUAUAAAAGUUUUUAGAGAGCCCUUUGUCUCCAAUUCAAAAUUGUUUUCAGCUAAUGAUGUAGAAAAUAUAUUUAGUCGCAUAGUAGAUAUACAUGAACUUAGUGUAAAGUUACUGGGCCAUAUAGAAGAUACAGUAGAAAUGACAGAUGAAGGCAGUCCCCAUCCACUAGUAGGAAGCUGCUUUGAAGACUUAGCAGAGGAACUGGCAUUUGAUCCAUAUGAAUCGUAUGCUCGAGAUAUUUUGCGACCUGGUUUUCAUGAUCGUUUCCUUAGUCAGUUAUCAAAGCCUGGGGCAGCACUUUAUUUGCAGUCAAUAGGCGAAGGUUUCAAAGAAGCUGUUCAAUAUGUUUUACCCAGGCUGCUUCUGGCCCCUGUUUACCACUGUCUCCAUUACUUUGAACUUUUGAAGCAGUUAGAAGAAAAAAGUGAAGAUCAAGAAGACAAGGAAUGUUUAAAACAAGCAAUAACAGCUUUGCUUAAUGUUCAGAGUGGUAUGGAAAAAAUAUGUUCUAAAAGUCUUGCAAAACGAAGACUGAGUGAAUCUGCAUGUCGGUUUUAUAGUCAGCAAAUGAAGGGGAAACAACUAGCAAUCAAGAAGAUGAACGAGAUUCAGAAGAAUAUUGAUGGUUGGGAGGGAAAAGACAUUGGACAGUGUUGUAAUGAAUUUAUAAUGGAAGGAACUCUUACACGUGUAGGAGCCAAACAUGAGAGACACAUAUUUCUCUUUGAUGGCUUAAUGAUUUGCUGUAAAUCAAAUCAUGGGCAGCCAAGACUUCCUGGUGCUAGCAAUGCAGAAUAUCGUCUUAAAGAAAAGUUUUUUAUGCGAAAGGUACAAAUUAAUGAUAAAGAUGACACCAAUGAAUACAAGCAUGCUUUUGAAAUAAUUUUAAAAGAUGAAAAUAGUGUUAUAUUUUCUGCCAAGUCAGCUGAAGAGAAAAACAAUUGGAUGGCAGCAUUGAUAUCUUUACAGUACCGGAGUACACUGGAAAGGAUGCUUGAUGUAACAAUGCUACAGGAAGAGAAAGAGGAGCAGAUGAGGCUGCCUAGUGCUGAUGUUUAUAGAUUUGCAGAGCCUGACUCUGAAGAGAAUAUUAUAUUUGAAGAGAACAUGCAGCCCAAGGCUGGAAUUCCAAUUAUCAAAGCAGGAACUGUUAUUAAACUUAUAGAGAGGCUUACGUACCAUAUGUACGCAGAUCCCAAUUUUGUUCGGACAUUUCUUACAACAUACAGAUCCUUUUGCAAACCUCAAGAACUACUGAGUCUUAUAAUAGAAAGGUUUGAAAUUCCAGAGCCUGAGCCAACAGAAGCUGAUCGCAUAGCUAUAGAGAAUGGAGAUCAACCCUUGAGUGCAGAACUGAAAAGAUUUAGAAAAGAAUAUAUACAGCCUGUGCAACUGCGAGUAUUAAAUGUAUGUCGGCACUGGGUAGAGCACCACUUCUAUGAUUUUGAAAGAGAUGCAUAUCUUUUGCAACGAAUGGAAGAAUUUAUUGGAACAGUAAGAGGUAAAGCAAUGAAAAAAUGGGUUGAAUCCAUCACUAAAAUAAUCCAAAGGAAAAAAAUUGCAAGAGACAAUGGACCAGGUCAUAAUAUUACAUUUCAGAGUUCACCUCCCACAGUUGAGUGGCAUAUAAGCAGACCUGGGCACAUAGAGACUUUUGACCUGCUCACCUUACACCCAAUAGAAAUUGCUCGACAACUCACUUUACUUGAAUCAGAUCUAUACCGAGCUGUACAGCCAUCAGAAUUAGUUGGAAGUGUGUGGACAAAAGAAGACAAAGAAAUUAACUCUCCUAAUCUUCUGAAAAUGAUUCGACAUACCACCAACCUCACUCUGUGGUUUGAGAAAUGUAUUGUAGAAACUGAAAAUUUAGAAGAAAGAGUAGCUGUGGUGAGUCGAAUUAUUGAGAUUCUACAAGUCUUUCAAGAGUUGAACAACUUUAAUGGUGUCCUUGAGGUUGUCAGUGCUAUGAAUUCAUCACCUGUUUACAGACUAGACCACACAUUUGAGCAAAUACCAAGUCGCCAGAAGAAAAUUUUAGAAGAAGCUCAUGAAUUGAGUGAAGAUCACUAUAAGAAAUAUUUGGCAAAACUCAGGUCUAUUAAUCCACCAUGUGUGCCUUUCUUUGGAAUUUAUCUCACUAAUAUCUUGAAAACAGAAGAAGGCAACCCUGAGGUCCUAAAAAGACAUGGAAAAGAGCUUAUAAACUUUAGCAAAAGGAGGAAAGUAGCAGAAAUAACAGGAGAGAUCCAGCAGUACCAAAAUCAGCCUUACUGUUUACGAGUAGAAUCAGAUAUCAAAAGGUUCUUUGAAAACUUGAAUCCGAUGGGAAAUAGCAUGGAGAAGGAAUUUACAGAUUAUCUUUUCAACAAAUCCCUAGAAAUAGAACCACGAAACCCUAAGCCUCUCCCAAGAUUUCCAAAAAAAUAUAGCUAUCCCCUAAAAUCUCCUGGUGUUCGUCCAUCAAACCCAAGACCAGGUACCAUGAGGCAUCCCACACCUCUGCAGCAGGAGCCAAGGAAAAUUAGUUAUAGUAGGAUCCCUGAAAGUGAAACAGAAAGUACAGCAUCUGCACCAAAUUCUCCAAGAACACCGUUAACACCUCCGCCUGCUUCUGGUGCUUCCAGUACCACAGAUGUUUGCAGUGUAUUUGAUUCCGAUCAUUCGAGCCCUUUUCACUCAAGCAAUGAUACCGUCUUUAUCCAAGUUACUCUGCCCCAUGGCCCAAGAUCUGCUUCUGUAUCAUCUAUAAGUUUAACCAAAGGCACUGAUGAAGUGCCUGUCCCUCCUCCUGUUCCUCCACGAAGACGACCAGAAUCUGCCCCAGCAGAAUCUUCACCAUCUAAGAUUAUGUCUAAGCAUUUGGACAGUCCCCCAGCCAUUCCUCCUAGGCAACCCACAUCAAAAGCCUAUUCACCACGAUAUUCAAUAUCAGACCGGACCUCUAUCUCAGACCCUCCUGAAAGCCCUCCCUUAUUACCACCACGAGAACCUGUGAGGACACCUGAUGUUUUCUCAAGCUCACCACUACAUCUCCAACCUCCCCCUUUGGGCAAAAAAAGUGACCAUGGCAAUGCCUUCUUCCCAAACAGCCCUUCCCCCUUUACACCACCUCCUCCUCAAACACCUUCUCCUCACGGCACAAGAAGGCAUCUGCCAUCACCACCAUUGACACAAGAAGUGGACCUUCAUUCCAUUGCUGGGCCGCCUGUUCCUCCACGACAAAGCACUUCUCAACAUAUCCCUAAACUCCCUCCAAAAACUUACAAAAGGGAGCACACACACCCAUCCAUGCACAGAGAUGGACCACCACUGUUGGAGAAUGCCCAUUCUUCCUGAGUUCCUCUGUACUGGGAUGUAUAUUUUCCUAGCCCCAAAUCCAUUGCUGGCAAUGGAUGCACUGAAUGUGCCAGCACUGAGGAGUUAAAAUGAGAACUCCAAACACUAACGACUCUUCUUCAAGAUGCAGUAUAAGACAAUGAAUUUUAACCUAGAUGUAAUUAUACAAUGGAAAUGGUAUUCCAGUUUAGAAUAUGGAAAGACCGACCUAGAGGAAUUGGACAACUGAUUGCACCUGAAAAUCAUAAAGGGACUUUUUCUGGCCAAUAGGCAGGAGUCCUCUUUUUGUGAAGUGAUCUUUUGUGAAGUGAUCAUUAAAGGGAUGGAAAACACAGUCUAGUGUCCAGCAGGCCCACAUGACAGUUUUUGUAAUUCAAAUUAUGCACUUUUAAAAAAAAAAACUUAAACAGGGAUCUUAAUAUCUUCCUUUGUUUUCCUUUGCUUUACUCUUCUACUUUAGAAUAUUUUCUUAAAAAUCACUCAAAGGACUGUGAGGAAAGGCUGUGGUACCUGACCUUGUUGAAAUCAAGGCCCGGCACUGUACUACAGGCCUGUUUACAGAUUAUUACGGUGAACUGAAUGGGUACCGAGGCUUCACCAAAGAGGUACUUUUUUGUUGUUGUUGUUGUUUUAGGAAUAAUUGUACCAAUUUUAAGAGCAUUCCCCCCACCUGUCCCCACACACCCAAACAAAAUGUGGUGGUGUUGCCUUCAAAAAAGAGAAGUUUUGUGUCAUUAACAUGACAGAAGAACUUUUUAAAAAAAAAUAACUGUCAACUAUUCUAUUUGCAUUUAGGAGACUGUUCAUCUAUGCUAGAUUGUCAUUUUCCCUCCUUCUCCCACAGAAGUUUACUGGUAGUCCAUGUCAUGGCUCGUAGCUAUCCCUCUAACCAUACCAUGGAAAUGCAGGCACCCAAUGUGAAAAGGAGCACUUGCUGGGCAUCACUGACACCGCUCAUGUUUUACACAUAGUUGAGUAAUCAGCAUAUCUAGAAUUAUCUUGCAUUGCCUAAAUCAUAUGUAUAUAGUGAAUGUUAUAUAAUAUACCUGGCAGGUCUGUUUUAAUUUAAUUGAAUAAAGAUACAAAUACUUUGUUUGGCUGGCAUAUAUUAAAUUAUUAUAUGAAGAAAAUGGUUGAUUCUUAUUUCUUUUAGUUGAAAAACACACAAAAACACUAAACAUAAAAGCACGUUUUGUGGUACGCCUUGGUUUCUAGUUCUGGAUAUAUGUAUUAAUCUUAAAGAAUGAUCUAAAGUCACAGCUUGGCAUAUAGGAAGAUACUUGGUUAGAAUAGGAUGGGUAUCUUUUAAGCAGAACUUUGUAAGUAAGUUUUAAGUUCCUAAGCAACAAGUAUACAGUUUGUUAAGGUUUAUAUUGAACAUUCUACCUUGCUUGAGGUUUUCUGCUUUAUCAAAACUAUUCAUAAUAGAACAUCUACCUGCAUCAUUACUAUCAUAAUAUGGAUUAUUCAUAAAGCGUAUGUACUGUUCUUCUGAGUCUAACAAAUACUGUGACUGAAAUGCAUGCACCUUGUUGAAGAGAAAACAUUUUAUUAAUCUCCACUAUAAUGUCUGUGAAAUGUGCAGUAUUCCAUCCUUAGAGAGUUUAUCUGGUUCAUCAGCAUCUGCAUGUAUCCUCUGAAUAAUGAAGCAACAUUUCAGCAAUUCUGUUAACCACACCAUUAGAGACAUUUUUAGAAGUGCUGCAACAUGGUGGGAACCUAGUACUUUAAUAAUUUCCUAUGAUAUUUAUUAGAGCAUAAAAUGUACAUCACGAUAGUACAGUAUGUAGUCCUUUAAGACCAGAAGGUAUGUUAACUGCACCAUCAUUAAGCAGUCUAUCCUAUUUUCUUAUUUAUUUGUUAGAAUUGAAUCCUUUCUCAAUAUCUGUACCAUUCCUAUGAUGGUAGCCAUUCUUCUCUUUAUAAAAUAUUUCCUCUUUGAAAAGCGUCCUAAAACAUUAAUUUCAAAUCCCCUCUUGGAUGCAAAGUGUCCCUAAGACCAUCCAUUCAACAGUAUUUAUGUGAGCCAACUUACUAGAGCCGCUACAACUAAUCAUGAUAGACAGUCCAGAAUCUCCCUGGACUUUAUACUGGGCCAGCCUCAUUGUCCCUAAGAUUUCUCUUUUUAUGUCUCAUGGAUUACUUCUCUUUUUAAUUGCCCCAGGCACAUUCCAAAUGAGAACCUGGUAAAAGUCACAUUGGACCCCCUUCAGUAUGUCUUCGGCUAAUGUGUUAGCCUUCAAUAAGGUGAUAACCCCUUUUCAACCUAUCUAGUCUAUAAAGAGGAAAAAUUCAGAUUUGGAGUUCUAAUCCUAUUUCUCCCAAAGGGAACUAUUCUUCUACCCCAUGGUUCUAGGAGACCACUUCACUGUGCAACAGUUUUACAUGCAUUGUGGAUGGAGGAUAUUUUUAUUCUGAACUGUUACAUUUAGGUAAAAAUAUUUUCUGCAGUGGUAACUGAUUAGAAAAAUGCCAAUUGGAUGCCCUUAGGUGGAGGUGAGAAAAUGGCAUCCUUGCCUUCUUCUCAAUAUGAAACAUUAACUAGUUGACAAAUUUAUCCUUGUAGUAAUGAAAAUCUAUUUAAUCAGGGACCAGAAAUGGCUGAGGAGAUAAAUGCAUCAUUACAAAAUUCUGCUUUUGAAUCCUGGACAUUACAAGGGGGUAAAUGCAGCAUGACUUUUUGUUAACCACAUUCCAAAAUGUGGAACAUUUCUUUUAGAAAUGAAAAUAUUUCAAGGCUGAUGUAUUUUAAGACUACACAUUAUCAGGAAACAUACAUUGAGAGUUCGCUUAAUUAAAGGUUGUUGGGCAUCAAAUUAUGUUUAGUAGGUUACUAUUCUCUAACAACUCAAGGAUGCUUUAAUGGAUCUGAAUUUGACAAAGAGCAUGCCACACUAAUACUACAGUCAACAACAGCCCAGAGAACAAUUACUAUGUCAGCUGGAGGCUAUAUUAUGAUUCUAAAUUCUUAAAGGUUUUUUUCCCUCCAUAAAUCAAAAAUUACCUUAUGUAAACCAAAAAUUAGUUGGUAUUUAUGGUCAUGAUCUUAAUUCUCAAGUUUAGCUUAAUCUUGUAUUUCAUUGUUUGUCUUCUAAUAUGACAGCUUAAAUUCAGAUUUUUAAGUGACUCAGCAAAAUAGGAGGAGUGUCCCAAUUUAUUAGUGUUGUACAUAUUGAAGAAAACCUUUUUGUUCCUUCAGAUUUAGAAAGAAACAGUUUAACCAUUUAUUUCUUGGUAUUCUGCUGCUGUGAAUAGGUUUACUUAUUCUUUUAACAUAUAUUGUGUGACUACGCAAGUAUAGGUCCUGUUGUAUUGCAUUAAUCUUUACCAGUAACUAAACAUCACAAGGUUAAUAUUGGUUUGGCUGAAAGAAUUAUGCAGUAAAGUUAUUUAUAAGGGAACAUGAUGACUUUAUUCAAUAUUUUUCUUCUUUGAAACAUCUCAUUACUAACUUUUAAGAUUAUUUCAUAAUCCCUUAUACAUGAGCCAAUGAAAUAUUUUGAGCUCUACUUAAGAAGCAUGAAGUCUAUAUUAUAAAUCUAAACAACAAAAGCACUUGUAACUUGUUUAGUAAAUUCCAUGCCUUAUUUUCCAUUUUUGACACCGUAAAGUGCAUUUUCUGUCGACUGUGAGCAAAUUUCCCUUUUGCCUUUAAUGAAAAUAGUGCAUUAAGUAGCCAAUUGCUGCAGAAUUAUAAAGCAAAUUAGCUAACAGUGGGUCACAUUGGACUACCACUCAAAGAAACAAGAUGCAUAACAGAUGAUGGAAGGUACAUGUGGUGUGGCUUAGGGAGAGCGCACCUGUGCCAGAUGCAUGCCACUUUCAGUAGCUGCCAAAUGUGCCUUUAAUUAAGAACAUCUCUAAUUUUUUUCUUCAGAUCAAGUCAGCAUUUGGGGUCGGGAUUUGGGCAGGGAACUUUGGGGUGCAAAUAUCUGGUGAAACCACCAGAGAAUUUGUUUGUCAAAGUGACAUGUAUAAUUUUAGUUGAGACGUGUUUGUGUAUAUAUGUGUAUUUGCCUUUGUUUAGUAGCACGGUUAUUUGCUAAAAUAAUUGUCAAAAAAUUGCUCUGUCGGUCGGUCUUUGAUGUAAGAACAAAGUGUGGUCUAUACAUCUAAUAUGGCCUUUGUACCUAACCAUGUUCAUAGGUAAUCUUUGUACUCUGUGUGCAGCAGUAUUUGGUUUGCAUUUAAAGUGAAAAUAACGGCUGUUAUUUUUCUGGCAUUACUAAGAUAAACUGAAAAAUAAUAAAGAAAAAUGCCUUACAUAGCCCACAA